GUUUCUCUCACAGACUGUGUACAGUGCCCUGGGCCUGAGGGAUGCCUGCCGCUCCCUGCCGCAGUCCAUCCAGCUCUUUCGGGACAUUGCCCAAGAGUUCUCUGAUGACCUGCACCAUAUCGCCAGCCUCAUUGGGAAAGUAGUGGACUUUGAGGGCAGCCUUGCUGAAAAUCGCUUCACAGUCCUCCCCAACAUAGAUCCUGAAAUUGAUGAGAAAAAGCGAAGACUGAUGGGACUUCCCAGUUUCCUUACUGAGGUUGCCCGCAAGGAGCUGGAGAAUCUGGACUCCCGUAUUCCUUCAUGCAGUGUCAUCUACAUCCCUCUGAUUGGCUUCCUUCUUUCUAUUCCCCGCCUGCCUUCCAUGGUAGAGGCCAGUGACUUUGAGAUUAAUGGACUGGACUUCAUGUUUCUCUCAGAGGAGAAGCUGCACUAUCGUAGUGCCCGAACCAAGGAGCUGGAUGCAUUGCUGGGGGACCUGCACUGCGAGAUCCGGGACCAGGAGACGCUGCUGAUGUACCAGCUACAGUGCCAGGUGCUGGCACGAGCAGCUGUCUUAACCCGAGUAUUGGACCUUGCCUCCCGCCUGGACGUCCUGCUGGCUCUUGCCAGUGCUGCCCGGGACUAUGGCUACUCAAGGCCGCGUUACUCCCCACAAGUCCUUGGGGUACGAAUCCAGAAUGGCAGACAUCCUCUGAUGGAACUCUGUGCCCGAACCUUUGUGCCCAACUCCACAGAAUGUGGUGGGGACAAAGGGAGGGUCAAAGUCAUCACUGGACCCAACUCAUCAGGGAAGAGCAUAUACCUCAAACAGGUAGGCUUGAUCACAUUCAUGGCCCUGGUAGGCAGCUUUGUGCCAGCAGAGGAGGCCGAAAUUGGGGCAGUAGACGCCAUCUUCACACGAAUUCAUAGCUGCGAAUCCAUCUCCCUUGGCCUCUCCACCUUCAUGAUCGACCUCAACCAGCAGGUGGCGAAAGCAGUGAACAAUGCCACUGCACAGUCGCUGGUCCUUAUUGAUGAAUUUGGAAAGGGAACCAACACGGUGGAUGGGCUCGCGCUUCUGGCCGCUGUGCUCCGACACUGGCUGGCACGUGGACCCACAUGCCCCCACAUCUUUGUGGCCACCAACUUUCUGAGCCUUGUUCAGCUACAACUGCUGCCACAAGGGCCCCUGGUGCAGUAUUUGACCAUGGAGACCUGUGAGGAUGGCAACGAUCUUGUCUUCUUCUAUCAGGUUUGCGAAGGUGUUGCGAAGGCCAGCCAUGCCUCCCACACAGCUGCCCAGGCUGGGCUUCCUGACAAGCUUGUGGCUCGUGGCAAGGAGGUCUCAGACUUGAUCCGCAGUGGAAAACCCAUCAAGCCUGUCAAGGAUUUGCUAAAGAAGAACCAAAUGGAAAAUUGCCAGACAUUAGUGGAUAAGUUUAUGAAACUGGAUUUGGAAGAUCCUAACCUGGACUUGAACGUUUUCAUGAGCCAGGAAGUGCUGCCUGCUGCCACCAGCAUCCUCUGAGAGUCCUUCCAGUGUCCUCCCCAGCCUCCUGAGACUCCGGUGGGCUGCCAUGCCCUCUUUGUUUCCUUAUCUCCCUCAGACGCAGAGUUUUUAGUUUCUCUAGAAAUUUUGUUUCAUAUUAGGAAUAAAGUUUAUUUUGAAGAAA